AGGUUAAGAGCAGAGGUUUACUAGGCCAAAGAAAGAGAAUAGCUCUCUGUUGCAGAGAGGGGUCCUGGAGAAAUGGGUUACCCCAGUUGUCUUAUUUAAAUGGUUACCCAUCAGAUUUUAAUUUUAUCUUCUCUUUGAGAGCUUGGUAAUAAGAAGCACUUAAAUCACUCCAAAGAAGACUUUAAAAAGGGAGCAGUGAAAAGGUCUUAAUAAUUUAUUGAUUGAAUUAAGAAAUACUAGCUAAUUAAGAAUCUGAGUCUAAACAGCACAGAUUUUUUCUUUCUGCUUUUAAAUUGUGUUUUAAAAAAAGAGACAGGGGGCUGGGCGUGGUGGCUCACGCCUGUAAUCCUAGCACUUUGGGAGGCCGAGGCGGGUGGAUCACGAGGUAGGAGUUAAAGACCAGCCUGGCCAACAUGGCAAAACCCUACUAAAGAUACAAAAAAAAAAAAAAAUUAGCCAGGCGUGGUGGUGGGUGCCUGUAAUCCCAGGUACUUGGAAGGCUGAGGCAGGAGAAUCUCUUGAACCCAGAAGGCGAAGGUUGCAGUGAACCGAGAUCAUGCCAUUGUACUCUAGCCUGGGUGACAAGAGCAAGACUCCGUCUCAAAAAAAAAAAAAAAAAAAAAAAGAAGUAGAGACAGGGAGACAGGGUCUCACUGUGUUGCCUAGGCCGGUCUUGAACUCCUGGGCUCAAGUGAUUCUCCCACCUUGACCUCCUAAAUUGUUGGGAUUACAGGUGUGAGACAGUGCACCUGGCCGAAAUAGCUCAAGUUUCUGAAAAACAAAUCUGAAUCUAUUUGUUAUUCUUAGCGUCACUGGUCUGGCUUUCAGAAUUAACAUACAAGGUUGCCACACCUAGUUCUGCCCAGCUUUAUGUCUUUUAUUCCAGUAUUCCACCAAAGUUUGUUUUCCUGCAUUCCAGUUCUCAAGUCUUAAGAUAAAGAUUGUACUUGACAGUUUAGUAUAUCCAUAAAACUAUUUGAGGUGGUUAAGGUUCUUGGGUUCAUUUUCCUUAAUACUUUGCUGAAUAUUGUAGAUUGUAGGCAAUGAAAAAGUCUACUAAAUUAGGAAAACCUUGAAUAAUUAGGUAUCCUAGGUAAGAGCCCCUAAACAUCAAGCAAUCUGUGAGUCUGUAAAGAAAUAAAUAUUUUUUGGAUUAUUCUUAUCUAAUUCCACCCCUGUUGGAAGAUGAUUUCUUUGUUCUUUGCAACUAUGGAAGCUGUGAAAAUCAUCACAAGUGCCUCUGAAAGCGAGUGUUAGGUUGGUUAGAGGGUUUAAUAUUUUCUGCAAUGGUUUGUAGGAAUUUUAAUAAAUGUAGUAUAUUUUCUGAGAUGAUUUUGUAAAAGUACUAUUUUAAAUAUCAAAUCAACCAAUAAAUUCACAUUUGUGUUAGGAACAGAAAUAUGGUUUAUAUCUUUGCUGGCUUGGUUUCCUUUUUCUUAAUGUCUCUGGGAGGCUUAUUCCUUCAUUGUGGAAAUUUUAGCUAUUUAAACAUGUAAAUUUUUCUUUCUACAGCCAGGUAACUAUAAACACAGCCAAUAGAUUUUACACAAAGCAAUCCUAGAAGUAUCAGAAUGGGUUUUGAAAAGUUCAAGUCCAUCAUGUGAUCAUGUUUGGCUACUUUAAAAAAGCAAAAAAGUUCAAGUCUAACGAUCCCAUUUGUGAAAUCCACAGAGCAGAAAGAAAGGAAGCUUUUACUAUUUUAACUAUCUCUUGAACGUGAAAAGUUAUUGAUGCAGUGAGGUCGAAUGCACACCUACUGCUUCCUAAGCUCUGGAACAUGAAUCUCCUUCCUCUGUCAUCUCCCCAGAAUUGGAACCUCCUUAAUCCAACCAUCUCACUAUUGGUCAGUCUAGUGAUUGAGAAAUAGGAAAAGCCACAGGUUGAAAUGAUGAAAUGUCAUUACACUGAAAGAUAAUACCAAAGUACAAAGUCCUAGGCACAGUCUUGUCAAUUCCCUCUUGUCUAAGUGGUGUGGCAAAUAUUAUUGUCACUUUUCAGAGAAAACUGAGGUGUAGAGAAAUAAAUAAAUGAAGUUUUUUACAGUCAUUCCACAAGUUACUGAGCAAGUCUUAGAAGCCCUGACUCCCCAAACCACAAAAUCUCCUUUGAUAAUCAUUGCUGCCAUAACACCUUCUUUUACUGCUUUCCUCCUUGAAUCCAGAGAACACAUAUUUAUAAUCAUUUUAAGAGCCUGAGGAAAUGACUUCAGCCUGUGCAAAAGGGAGAAAGAAAAAAAGGCAAAACAUGUCCAAUGUCUUUUAGGUCCUAUAUUGGUUAGGAAUCCUUUGAUUCCAAGUGACAGAAUCCCAAUCCAAACAGACUUAAGCAGAAAAAGGACUAUCAACUCAAAUUAGUGAAAAUCAUACAGGCAGAAAGCCUCAGGCACAGCCUGAACAGGGCUCAGAUAAUGUUAUCAGGAGCCAGACAAUCUCUAGGGUCAUGUCUGUCCUCCCCUCUGCUCUAUUAGGUAGCAAGUUGGUAGAAAUGGCUCUGACCUUCAUGCUUCCAGGGCACAAGCCCAGUUAGAAAGAGCAAGCCUACUUUUUGUGGCCAUACCAGACCAAUCUGAUUUAACCUUUAUGUAACAAAGUUGUGAGUUGUUUUUCAGUUGCCAAUGGACCCUCAGGUCAUGUGCCCUGAGCACACCCAGAUGAACCAAGCCUGCAACCACAGGGGGAACCUAAGCUAAGUGCUCAGUCCAAGGAUGGGGACUGAAUUAAGAAGCAGACACAUGGGAGGAUCCAUGACCGAUCAGAUCAAGCUGUGGUAUCACCCCAUGGCAGGAUCCAGUCAGAUCAUGCCUCCCGGCAUCACCUCAUUGCAAGAUCCAAUCAGAUCAUGCCUCAUUACCCUAUACUUACAAAACCUGACCAAGCCCCCAGCUCUGGGAGAUACUGCUCUGGGAGAUACAGCCCUGGCAUUCUCCUUACUUGUUGCAAGUAAUAAAAUCCCCUUGCUAAAUGCUCCUUGGUUGUGGUCAUUGGGUUGAAUUUGCAAUGGAUGCUAGGAAGGCACAUAACAAAUAUACAUUAUAAACCCAUUGCUGGAUUUCACCGGAUUUGGAUCAGACCCUGUCUGUCUUCCUAUGGGAGAUCAUAUAGUACAAUGCUUAGAACACUGGAUUUUCAGUGGGAUAACUGCUUGCAACAAAGAAAGUAAAAGACAAAUUGAAACACUGGCUUUGGCAUCAAAGUGACAUGGUCAAGUCCUGGUUGUGUCAUUGGUUGAGUCUGUGACCUUGAGCAAGUUAUCUGUUUUUUCAUCUGUAAAUGGGGGUAUCUACCUAAAAGGUUAUGCUGAGGAGUAAAUGAAGCAAUGCACUUGGCACUUAAUAUAGGUUGACUUCAUUCAACAGAUAUUUAUUGAGUGUCUACUGUGUGCUCUGCUCUUAGUGCCUGGCUUAGAGCCCUGAAUAACUAGACAUAUCCCUGCCUGCGUGGAGCAUACAAUGAUGAUAAAUGUUUUCUAUAGAUGAGGAAGAAGCUCAGGGUGCCCAGCGAAUGUAAUCUGACCUAUCCAAGAGGAGAAGCUCUGAGGCUUUCUUGAGGAAGUAACAUCUGAGCUGAAUUCCAAAGAAUGAAAAAAGAAUAUUUCAGUCAACUAGAAUAGCUCGUGCCACAGCCAAGUGAAAGGAGGAAACACACUAUAUUCAAGGAAAUGAAAGAAACCAGACAGGGCUGGGCACCAGAGCCUCAAGGGCAGAUUCUAGGAUGGUUACUAUUUCCAUCAGUUUCUUCCUAAAUCUUGUUAAGACCCUGGGACAAUGAGCCAAAUGCUUAUUUUAAUGGCUGACACACACACACACACACAAAGGUACAUUAAAAUGUCUUAUAUUCUGAAACAUUUUUUAUUCCCAAGUGUUCUAAUAUUCAAAUUGUUUCAUCUGAAUUCCUACAUAGUUCAAACUUGAAUAGAAAGUAAAGCAGACAUUGCCUAAUAGUUCCUUUUGUACUCUUGAUCGUACCAUAAGCCUUCCCCUUUCGUCUUGGUUUAGAAAACACAGAACUUAACAUAACUGAAAUUCUUGUUUAUCUGUUAAAGUAAUUAAAAGUCUGAUGAAUCAUAGCAAACCAGUACCAACAAAAGCAAAAAGGCAAACUGUUCAGUAUCACUUUAACUCUCUCAAUAUUUAAAACCAGAAGCAUUAGGCUACAUUAAAAAAUAAAAAGAAUUCCCUGUUGAACUGUGGAGCCACUGGUUAAUCCCAGUGCCAGAGAAACGGAGCAGAGGUCACCUGAACAAAGGGCAAAGUAAAUAAUGAACCAGCAAUGUGCAAGGUAUUAUUUUGUUUCUAAAGGAAACCAUCUUGGGAACCUGCAGAGAACUACAUGGUAACAUAUAUGUGAACUAGGAAAAUUACCAUUCAGAAUUUACCGUUUUUUGUUUUGUUGUUUUUUGAGACACGGUCUCCCUCUGUGGCCCAGGCUGUAAUGAGGUGGUGUGAUCAUGGCUCACUGCAGCUUCAAUCUCCCAGGCCCAAGUGAUCAUCCUGCCUCAGGCUCCUAAGUAGCUGGGACCACAGGCAUGCACCAGCACACCUGGUUAAUUUUUUUAUUUUUAGUAGAGAUAGGGUCUCACCGUGUUGCCCAGGCUGGUCUCAAACACCUAGGCUUAAGUGAUCCUCCCUCCUCAGCCUUCCAAAGUUCUGGGAUUACAGGCAUUAGCCACCACACCCAGCCCCAGAAUUUAACAUUCUUAAAAGUAAAAAGCAUGAUAGUCUUACUUGAGGCUGCAUGUUUCUCAAUCUUUAAACAUGUAUCUGACACUGCCGGGCACAGUGGCUCGUGCCUGUAAUCCCUGCACUUUGGGAGGCCAAGGUGGGCAGAUUACCUGAGGUCAAGAGUUCAAGACCAGCCUGGCCAACAUGUUGAAACCUCAUCUCUACUAAAAAUACAAAAAGUUAGCCGGGCGUGGUGGAGGCCACCUGUAAUCCCAGCUACUUGGGAGGCUGAGGCAGGAGAAUUGCUUGAACCUGGGAGGCAGAGGUUGCAGUGAGCCAAGAUCACACCAUUGCACUCCAGCCUGGGCAACAAGAGCAAAACACCGUCUCAAAAAAAAAAAAAAAAUGUACCUCACACUGAUGUCAAUCUUCUCUUUGGAAUAAUCCUUUUAUUCCAUGUCCCAAAUAUCUAAUAAUUUCCAUUUCUUAAGUAUCUUCUUUAUGCAAGGCACUAUUUAUUUAUAGAGACAGGAUCUUGCUAUGUUGCCCAGGCUGGUCUCAAACUCCUGGGCUCAAGCAAUUCUCAAGUCUCAGCCUCCCAAAGUGCUGUGAUUACAGGCAUGAGCUAUCACACUCAGCUGGCAUUAACUUUUUAAACAAUUAUUUCACAUAGUACUUAUAACUCUACAAGACAGGGAUAAUUAUCCCCAUUUGACAAAUGAGAAAACAGAUUUGCAUAUUUCUUGUCCAAGGCCAUGAAGUGAGUGUCCACACCAGUGUUCCCAUGCAGUUUGCCUGACUCAGAAGCCCAGGCCUCCCCCACUACACUGUAUAGCUUCCCAAGAUCAUCUUCUGAGUCCAAGAUCUCCAUAUUUGUCUCUUCUCUCCUCCACCAUUUCACUGUGAUGGUCUCCUGAGACUCAUUUGUUCUGUAUUAUUCUAUGUUCAAUCCCUUGACCCUUUCUUCCACUCUUAGGUCAUGAAAAAUCACCUGUGUGAAGAUUCCUAAACCUCAUACUUUUGCCAAUCCUUUGAUAUUUAGAAUUUAACACAGCAAAACCAGAAUACACUGUCUCCUUUCCUAAAUAAAUAACACUGUCUAACUUCUCUACUACCUAUGAUUAUUUCUGUAUUAUUUAAGGAUCAGAUAAAGUGAUGCCCCUUCUACAAAGCAUUCUCUGGCUAUUUCAAGAAACUUCCUCUUUGAGAAAUCUCUUAUCACUAACACCCAGAGGUAUGAUUUCACACCAGCAAUUUCUUCUUUGUUUCUUCUACAUGUCAGACACAUUGCUUAUUACAUAGCACGUGCUCAAAAAGUAUUUACUGAUUAAAUCAUCAUAAGUACUGCCUGUUCUUCUGACAAGGAUUUUUUUGGUGCUGCUUUGCCAGACGCAGACCUCCAUGGCUAGUGACACCCCUGCCCAGGGCCUUACUCCACCCUGGGCUUGCCGCAGGAGACACCUGACCCCCUAAACCCAGCAGGGCUGCACUUGGCUUGUGCUCUGGCUCAGAUCCUGCAACUUUCUGUGGGAUCUGUACUCAGCCUGCAGCUGGGCCAGGUAUGCCAAGACCUGCCUCCAGCUUGGGCGUGGCAUCUGGACGAGGGGAAUGUGGUGACAUCACAAAAACUUGGAGGCACCAUUGACCCCGAAGCCUCAAAGUGGUGUUACAGCAUGUCACAGCCCUGGCUUGGGGAGCCCUUAGAUCUGGACUCCCAGAAGGGCCGCAGCUUUUCUUUCCUUCUCAUCGCCUGCAACGUGACGAGCAGGAAGGGUUGCAGAAGGGUGGUGUGUGCUUCAGUCCAUUUGUGUUGCAGCUCUUUCAGUCCCACCAUUCGGCGGGUCCCUCGGUGGGUCCCAAGUUCUUGUUCCGUGUCCUGGAACAAUGAGGUCCACAUGGCUGCAGUCGGAGGGAGGCGGUGAGCAAGGUGUUCUCCAAGGUCUCAAGGGGCCCCAAGGCUACAAGCCUCUUGCUGAAGGAACAACAGGAGACAGACAGCAGGUGGCGGGGUGUGCCACAGAGAAAAAAAUGUCUUCAGAUAACCAGUGGUCAGCAGAUGAGGAUGAAGGCCAAUUAUCCCGACUAAUCAGGAAAUCUAGAGACUCCCCCUUUGUCCCUAUAGGUAUAGCAGGCUUUGUGACUGUGGUGUCCUGUGGUCUUUACAAGCUAAAGUACAGAAGAGAUCAGAAAAUGUCAAUUCAUCUUAUUCACAUGAGAGUUGCUGCCCAAGGAUUUGUUGUUGGAGCUGUGACUCUAGGUGUUCUCUAUUCUAUGUAUAAGGAUUACAUUAGACCACGAUUCUUCAGUGAGUCCAAAAAAUGAAGCUUACAUGCUGGAAGCAAGAAAGACAAGAAGCUUCUGAAAACUAUUUAUUAUGAAGAAUAAAUUUUCAAUAUGUAGCAAAUUUUACUACACAAGUGUCA